GUAACCUAAAGAAAAACAACCAGACAAGUGCCCAACGACACUUAAAAAGGUGAUUUAUUAUCUUGCCAAGUUUAGGCUGGGCAUGGUGACUCAUGCCUGUAAUCCCAGCAUUUUGGGAGGCUGAGGCUGGUGGAUCACCUGAGGCCAGGACUUCGAGACCAGCCUGACCAAUAUGGCAAAACCUCGUCCCUACUAAAAAUACAAAAAUUAGCCGGGCAUGGUGGUGUGAGCCUGUAGUCCCAGCUACUCAGGAGGCUGAGACAGGAGAAUUGCUUAGAUUCAGGAGGUGGGGGUUUUAGUGGGCCGAGAUCACGCCAUUGCACUCCAGACUGUGCGACAGAGCGAGACUCUGUCAAAAAAAAAAAAAAAUUAUCCUGCAAAAUUUGAAAAGGAAAUUCAAAUCAACAGCUUCUAAACUACUUUUUAACAUGACUCAUAAUAAGAAAUACAUUCUAUAGUACAUAUAUAUGUUCUAUAACUUUGAAUAAAAGAGUUAACCACAUCACAUUUAUUUUACAACAUGUAAUACAUAUUUUUUAUUCUCCUUCAUUUGUUUUGAAUGCUCUGUUUAGUCUACAAAAAGUCCAAUAGUAAUAAUUAAAUUAGUCAUUAAGUUGAACAUUAUCUUGUCUUUUAAAAUGAUAAUCUCAAAAAUGAUCUUUUAUUUUUGAGAUUUAUAUAGAUACACACACACACACACACACACACACACACACACACACACACACACACACACACAUAUAUUUUUUGAGACAGAGUUUCACUCUGUCCCCCAGGCUGGAGUGCAAUGGCACAAUCUUGGCUCACUGCAACCUCCGUCUCCCGGGUUCAAGCAAUUCCUCUGCCUCAGCCUCUGAGUAGCUGGGACUACAGGUGUGUGCCACCAUGCCCAGCUAAUUUUUGUAUUCUUAGUAGAGAUGGGGUUUCACCAUAUUGGCCAGGCUCGUGUCAACUCCUGACCUCGUGAUCUGCCCACCGCGGCCUCCCAAAGUGCUGGGACUUUAGGUGUGAGCCGCUGCACCCGGUCCAAGUAAAAUUAUUUUAACAAUAUACUAUGAAGAGAAAAACACUGGCUAUGAAAGAAUAUGCAUAGUUUUACCCUGUUUAAAAAUAAAGAUUGAAAGAAUACAUAUGCAAAUAAGUUUACUUUUAUUUUUGGUAACACUUUACUGCAUUGUCUGAAUAUUGACAAUCAGUAUGCAUUAUGAAGCUACCUGGCUAACAUUGUGUACUCACUGUGUGUGCCAGGCCCUGGGUUCAAUGCUCUACAUGCACUUAUAUUUCAUUUAAUUCUCUCUGCAACCUGAGAUGGUAUAGCCACCUCAUUUUACAGAGUUGAAACUGAGGCUCAGAGACUGAAAGUUAAGCCUGAGGUUGCAGUCAAUAAGAGGCAGAGCUGGAACUGAAACCUACCUGUGUCUGACCACCAGUUCGUGUUCUGACGGCAGGCUAGUCUGCAUCACAGAGUGUGGAGUAGAUGGUGCAUGCCUGCUAGGAUGGGCUAGGUAUCACUGUAGGUAAGAAACAGCCCCAAACUAUGGAAAUGUACACCACUGAAGGCUCUUUUCCUGCCCAUGCUGCACAUCCUCCAUGGCUCUCCUGUGCCCUGUGCCCCACAUGCCCUCAUCCUGCCACGAGAAUAAAGGAGCAGCCUCCAUAUGGGAGCUGUCAGCUGCUCUAAGAGAUGAAGGAGAGAGUGGCCCGUCUCAAUGGCUCCCAACUCUUUUGCCUCGAGGUGACACGCUUCACUUCCACUCACAUCUCCUGGGUCAAAGCAAAUCCCAUGGGUACAUCCACUUUCAAGUGGCCCAGGAGAGAACCUGAAAUACUCGGUGGACUCCAUUAAGGCCGUCAUAUGGUGUCAGCCUGCAUGGGAGACUGUGGAGGGGCAGAGGAGGAGAGUGGGGAACUGAUGGGAAAUGACAGGAGGACUAAGUCACCGCAGAUUUGCUUUAUCUUCAGCCAGGUGGAGUUUGUCCCAGAGCCGCACAAAAUCAUCACCAGCAUGAUUAAACGGAGUAGACUUCAGAAAAAGCAGUUUGGUCGGAUGUAAUCAGCAGUGAACUCAGAAUCAAUUGAGUGACAUUGAGUCAGUAAAUCUCUGACUGCCUCAGUUACCCCAUAUGAUAGUUUUGAGGAUGGGAACAUUGAGAGAGUUGAUUUGGAAGGAUAUCAAGAGUAAAAAUUCCAACAUUUUUAGUUCCUUUAAGUUAAAUCCAGGCACUGUCUUUCCUGCAAGUCUCCUGUUCCUUUCAGAUUGCACAGGUGAGAGUGCUCAGAUUAGGGCUGGAGGUUGUAAACCAUUGCUCCCACACUGACAGUGCCCCCGUGUCGUGCAUGUAUUCUGCGCAUUUUCCUGUGCUAAACACUCUCCCAAAACAUCGUGGGGCCUGAUUCUUCCUCUUUGUUCCAAUGGCCCUGGGUGACUCAAGUGCCCAUUCAAUGACCAGGACACAGAGGUCUUAGAGAGAUGCUCCUUGAGGCCCCAGGUGCGAGCCUGUACCCUGCCGGAGCAUGAGGCAAGGGACAGGGCAUCGUCUGUGGGGAUAGUGGGGGUAGUGGGGGUAGUGGUCAGCCAGAUUUGGUGACUCUACUUGCUCACCAGACGAUCCUACACCUGCCACCUCCGAUGGAUCCACUGCCUCUGUGCCUGCCUGUACUGCUGAUGCUCCAGUGGAUAACUCAGCAUCCCAGCCUAGGCCCAAUGCCACUGAAGAUGGACCUUCCCCCUGGGGACCCAGGAGUCCUACCACUCAGCUGUCCCCAGGAGUGCCCAGACCCUCAUUCUUAUCCAGGACCUAGGAGCCCUACCCCUGGCCUUCCCUCAUCAGCCGUAAAUGAUGAUUUACUGCUGUUACCAUCAUCACUGCCUUCAGUGACCAAGGGCCUUCCAAGGCGCCAGCUCUGGAACGAAGGAUGCCCUUGGGAGGUGAUGACACUCAGGUACACGGGUGCUCAACAGAUUGCUUCCUCCUAUCCUCAGACGGUCUUUGCAUGCAUGCAGCCAUUGGCACUCCCAUUGUGUGGAAGGAAACCAGCCCAGGGUCACACAGCUGGUCAGCAGCAACAUAGCUGUUCUCAAAUCUAAGGUGCCUGACCAUGCCUCCAUGAGGGACCGCCUCCAAGGGAGGUUGAUCCUGGCUUUGGGGAGCCUUUCCUGGGCUGCACGAAUAACCUCCAUUGUUCGAGACCCCAAACUCUGCUCACAUCUUCCUUUCCCUAUCUCUGCUUGGGCUAUGAUCACGGUGACUCUAGCAGCCCUUCAUGGACAUUAUAGUACUCUCUGCCAUUCACUUUUGCUCUAAUCUGACUUCAACCCCCACUUACUUGGUCUCUCCUUUUACAACCACCACAACCGAAAUCUAGGGCUGCUUUUUUUUUUUUUUUUUUUUGAGACAGAGUCUCAUUCCAUUCUGUCACCCAGGCUGGAGUGCAAUGGUACAAUCUCGGCUCACUGCAACCUCCGCCUCCCGGGUCCAAGGGAUUGUCCUGCCUCAGCCUCCUGAGUAGCUGGGAUUACAGGCGUGUGCCACCAUGCCUGGCUAAUUUUUGUAUUUUUAGUAGAGAUGGGGUUUCACCAUGUUGGUCAGGCUGGUCUCCAACUCCUAACCUCGUGAUCCGCCUGCCUCAGCCUCCCAAAGUGCUGGGAUUACAGGCGUGAGCCACCAUGCCCAGCCAAAUCUAGGGCAGGAACAUGGCUGCAGCAUAUAAAAAGAAUUGAAUUCCAUACUUUUGUUAACCCUGUUUUUUGUUUGUUUGUAGUUGUUGCUGUUUUUGAGACAGAGUCUCGCUCUGUCGCCUAGGCUGGAGUGCAGUGGUGCAAUCUCGGCUCACUGCAGACUCUGCCUCCCGGGUUCAAACUAUUCUCCUGCCUCAGCCUCCCAAGUAGGUGGGACUACAGGCGCCCACCACCACACCCGGCUAAUUUUUGUAUUUUAUUAGAGACAGGGUUUCACCAUAUUGGCCAGGCUGGUCUGGAACUCCUGACCUUGUGAUCCGCCCACCUCGGCCUCCCAAAGUGCUGGGAUUACAGGCGUGAGCCACCACACCCAGCCCCUGUUUUGUUUUUGUUUUGCUUGCUUCUUAGGGUUGUUUUUCUAUUUAUGGUAAAGGCAUUGGCUUUCCAUUUGUAGCAUCAAUAGAAUAUUUCCUGUUUACAAUAACCUUAUGUCAUAGUAAAUGGUAAAGGGAUUUAAAGCAGUGGUUUUCAGCUGCCAGAGGCCUGAGAGAGUUUGGGCAUACUCUGUGUGAUCGGGCAGAAGGCCUGUGGGAAGUUUAGCAGAGGACAGGGCCAGGAAAGUUGAUGGACAGUGGGGGUCUGUCCUGGUCACCAGGCCCCUGGGUCCUGCCCACCUGCUUGGAGCUCCCCACCCAUCACACAUGAUGCUGCCAAGCCCUCUGGGUAUUGUGGGCAAAUACCUUAGGAGAGAAGCUGAUGAACUUUGUUUCUUGAAAUGCACAGAUUCCUUGGACGUCCCUGAGAGCUCAGUCAUGAAAGUCAACUUGGUUUUCUCCCCCUCAUUUGGGUUCAGAAUUUAAAGUCCACACACACAGGCAGUAAGAUGAUAUAGAUAAGGACGUCAUCACUCGGUUUCGGAUGUUAAAAUGUCUAGGUGGGUUAGCGGUGAUUUGAGAUCACACAACCUUGUGCCACAAAGAGGAAUUCCCAGGCCAGAGGGAGACAUUUUAUUGCCAUGUUAUGAUCUCAUCAUUGAGUUGAAAGGCAAUCUUGUUUCAUUUUGGAUUCUUUCUUAUGUUUAUGUCUUAUAAGGGCACUUUGAAUUUCCAAGCAAAUAAUAAUUUUGAAUUAGCUUUUAAUCAUUGACUUCUAGCACAGUUAUAUGAUCAGAAACAUGCUGUGUGAUUUGAUUGCUCUCAAAUAUAUUGAGAUUUGCUGGAACAAAAUAAGUCAGGUUAAUUUUUGUAAAUGUACCAGGCAUGCUUAAAAUGAAUGUAUCUACAUUUGUUCCUGAGAUACAGGUUGAUGGACGGAUGGCUACAUGGAUGUGAUGGAGAUGGUUUACUAUCGGGACCUUCCGCACCCUGCUGAUGUUUUGUUGCUUAGGAUAUGAAUGGCUGAGCGGAGGCUGUAAAACCUGGCACUCUGCUUGGGUUAUCAAUACUCUGGCUGACCAUCAUCAUCGUGGGACUGACUUUGGUGGAAGUCCUUGGUUACAUGUCAUUAUUGCGUUUCCGACAAGUUAUAAAGUUGUCAUUACCCUCUGGAUAGUUUACCUUUGGGUGUCUCUCCUGAAGACUAUCUUCUGGUCUCGAAAUGGACAUGAUGGAUCCACGGAUGUACAGCAGAGAGCCUGGAGGUCCAACCGCCGUAGACAGGAAGGGCUGAGGUCCAUUUGUAUGCACACAAAGAAAAGAGUUUCUUCCUUUCGAGGAAAUAAAAUUGGCCUGAAAGACGUCAUUACUCUACGGAGACAUGUGGAAACAAAAGUUAGAGCUAAAAUCCGUAAGAGGAAGGUGACAACGAAAAUCAACCAUCAUGACAAAAUCAAUGGAAAGAGGAAGACCGCCAGAAAACAGAAAAUGUUUCAACGUGCGCAAGAGUUGCGGCGGCGGGCAGAGGACUACCACAAAUGCAAAAUCCCCCCUUCUGCAAGAAAGGCUCUUUGCAACUGGGUCAGAAUGGCGGCAGCGGAGCAUCGUCAUUCUUCAGGAUUGCCCUACUGGCCCUACCUCACAGCUGAAACUUUAAAAAACAGGAUGGGCCACCAGCCACCUCCUCCAACUCAACAACAUUCUAUAACUGAUAACUCCCUGAGCCUCAAGACACCUCCCGAGUGUGUGCUCACUCCCCUUCCACCCUCAGCGGAUGAUAAUCUCAAGACACCUCCCGAGUGUGUGCUCACUCCCCUUCCACCCUCAGCGGAUGAUAAUCUCAAGACACCUCCUGAGUGUCUGCUCACUCCCCUUCCACCCUCAGCGGAUGAUAAUCUCAAGACACCUCCUGAGUGUCUGCUCACUCCCCUUCCACCCUCAGCGGAUGAUAAUCUCAAGACACCUCCCGAGUGUCUGCUCACUCCCCUUCCACCCUCAGCUCCACCCUCAGCUCCACCCUCAGCGGAUGAUAAUCUCAAGACACGUGCCGAGUGUCUGCUCCAUCCCCUUCCACCCUCAGCGGAUGAUAAUCUCAAGACACCUUCCGAGCGUCAGCUCACUCCCCUUCCACCCUCAGCUCCACCCUCAGCAGAUGAUAAUAUCAAGACACCUACACCUGCCGAGCGUCUGCGGGGGCCGCUUCCACCCUCAGCGGAUGAUAAUCUCAAGACACCUUCCGAGCGUCAGCUCACUCCCCUUCCACCCUCAGCUCCACCCUCAGCAGAUGAUAAUAUCAAGACACCUGCCUUCCACCCUCAGCGGAUGAUAAUCUCAAGACACCUUCCGAGCGUCAGCUCACUCCCCUUCCACCCUCAGCUCCACUCUCAGCAGAUGAUAAUAUCAAGAUACCUGCUGAGCGUCUGCGGAUUCCGCUUCCACCAUCAGCCGAUGAUAAUCUCAAGACACCUUCCGAGCGUCAGCUCACUCCCCUUCCACCCUCAGCUCCACCCUCAGCAGAUGAUAAUAUCAAGACACCUGCCGAGCGUCUGCGGGGGCCGCUUCCACCCUCAGCGGAUGAUAAUCUCAAGACACCUUCCGAGCGUCAGCUCACUCCCCUUCCACCCUCAGCUCCACCCUCAGCAGAUGAUAAUAUCAAGACACCUGCCGAGCGUCUGCGGGGGCCGCUUCCACCCUCAGCGGAUGAUAAUCUCAAGACACCUUCCGAGCGUCAGCUCACUCCCCUUCCACCCUCAGCUCCACCCUCAGCAGAUGAUAAUAUCAAGACACCUACACCUGCCGAGCGUCUGCGGAGGCCGCUUCCACCCUCAGCGGAUGAUAAUCUCAAGACACCUUCCGAGCGUCAGCUCACUCCCCUUCCACCCUCAGCUCCACCCUCAGCAGAUGAUAAUAUCAAGACACCUGCCGAGCGUCUGCGGCGAGCGUCUGCGGGGGCCGCUUCCACCCUCAGCGGAUGAUAAUCUCAAGACACCUUCCGAGCGUCAGCUCACUCCCCUUCCACCCUCAGCUCCACCCUCAGCAGAUGAUAAUAUCAAGACACCUGCCGAGCGUCUGCGGGGGCCGCUUCCACCCUCAGCGGAUGAUAAUCUCAAGACACCUUCCGAGCGUCAGCUCACUCCCCUUCCACCCUCAGCUCCACCCUCAGCAGAUGAUAAUAUCAAGACACCUGCCGAGCGUCUGCGGGGGCCGCUUCCACCCUCAGCGGAUGAUAAUCUCAAGACACCUUCUGAGCGUCAGCUCACUCCCCUUCCACCCUCAGCUCCACCCUCAGCAGAUGAUAAUAUCAAGACACCUGCCGAGCGUCUGCGGGGGCCGCUUCCACCCUCAGCCGAUGAUAAUCUCAAGACACCUCCCUUAGCUACUCAGGAGGCUGAGGCAGAAAAACCACGCAAACCCAAGAGGCAGAGGGCGGCUGAGAUGGAACCACCUCCCGAACCCAAGAGGCGGAGGGUCGGUGACGUGGAACCGUCACGCAAACCCAAGAGGCGGAGGGCCGCUGACGUGGAACCAUCAUCACCCAAACCCAAGAGGCGGAGGGUCGGUGAUGUGGAACCGUCACGCAAACCCAAGAGGCGGAGGGCCGCUGACGUGGAACCAUCAUCACCCGAACCCAAGAGGCGGAGGGUCGGUGACGUGGAACCGUCACGCAAACCCAAGAGGCGGAGGGCCGCUGACGUGGAACCAUCAUCACCCGAACCCAAGAGGCGGAGGUUGAGCUGAGAAGAGGCCAGUGCACUCAAGCCUGAGCAAUAAGAAUAAAACCGAGUAGAACA